GCCCGCCACGCUGUCGGCGCUAUAGCAACGGUAGCUAGCUGCAGGGCCAGUGGCACGCUAGGCCAUGUCUGGUCCAACUGAUGAGACUGCAGGAGACUUGCCUGUGAAAGAUACAGGUCUAAACCUCUUUGGAAUGGGAGGGUUACAAGAAACUUCAACAACACGGACAAUGAAGUCUCGCCAGGCAGUGUCACGUGUCAGUCGUGAGGAACUGGAAGACAGAUUUUUGCGUUUGCAUGAUGAGAACAUUUUACUUAAACAGCAUGCCCGCAAGCAGGAGGAUAAAAUUAAAAGAAUGGCCACCAAGUUAAUACGGCUAGUUAAUGACAAGAAAAGAUAUGAGCGGGUUGGUGGCGGCCCCAAGCGGCUGGGACGAGAUGUGGAAAUGGAAGAAAUGAUUGAGCAGCUGCAAGAGAAAGUUCAUGAGCUUGAAAAACAAAAUGAAACCCUCAAAAACAGACUGAUUUCAGCCAAACAGCAACUUCAAACCCAGGGUUACAGGCAAACUCCAUACAAUAAUGUACAAUCUCGUAUUAACACUGGGCGUAGAAAAGCAAAUGAAAAUGCUGGUUUACAGGAAUGCCCCAGGAAAGGUAUAAAAUUCCAAGAUGCAGAUGUAGCAGAAACUCCACAUCCCAUGUUUACAAAAUAUGGCAACAGUUUACUUGAAGAAGCCAGAGGAGAAAUAAGAAAUUUAGAAAACGUUAUUCAGUCACAAAGAGGCCAGAUAGAGGAGUUAGAGCACUUGGCUGAGAUCCUGAAAACUCAGUUGAGGAGAAAAGAAAAUGAAAUUGAGUUAUCUCUUCUUCAGCUUCGAGAACAGCAAGCUACAGAUCAAAGGUCAAAUAUUCGGGACAAUGUAGAAAUGAUUAAGCUUCAUAAACAGCUAGUAGAGAAAAGCAAUGCUCUUUCAGCAAUGGAAGGAAAAUUUAUUCAGCUUCAAGAGAAGCAAAGAACUCUCAGAAUCAGCCACGAUGCUUUGAUGGCAAAUGGGGAUGAAUUAAACAUGCAACUUAAAGAGCAGCGUUUAAAAUGCUGCAGUCUUGAGAAACAAUUACAUUCUAUGAAGUUUUCUGAAAGAAGAAUAGAAGAGCUGCAGGAUAGAAUUAAUGAUUUAGAAAAGGAACGGGAACUUUUAAAGGAAAACUAUGAUAAACUUUAUGACAGUGCCUUCAGUGCUGCCCAUGAAGAGCAAUGGAAGUUAAAGGAGCAACAGCUGAAAGUGCAGAUUGCUCAGCUCGAGACUGCCUUGAAGUCUGACUUAACAGACAAAACUGAAAUCCUUGACAGAUUAAAAACUGAAAGAGAUCAAAAUGAAAAACUCGUUCAAGAGAAUAGAGAACUACAGUUACAGUAUCUGGAACAAAAGCAACAACUUGAUGAACUUAAAAAACGCAUAAAAUUGUACAACCAGGAGAAUGAUAUUAAUGCUGAUGAAUUGAGUGAAGCUCUCCUACUUAUAAAGGCUCAAAAAGAACAAAAAAAUGGAGACCUUUCCUUUUUAGUGAAAGUAGAUAGUGAAAUUAAUAAAGAUCUAGAACGCUCUAUGAGAGAGCUGCAAGCAACUCAUGCAGAAACGGUGCAAGAGCUGGAAAAGACAAGAAACAUGCUAAUUAUGCAACACAAAAUUAAUAAAGAUUAUCAGAUGGAGGUUGAGGCAGUGACCCGUAAGAUGGAAAAUUUGCAGCAAGAUUAUGAACUCAAAGUGGAACAGUAUGUUCAUCUUCUUGAUAUCAGGGCUGCACGUAUCCAUAAACUAGAAGCCCAAUUAAAGGAUAUUGCCUAUGGCACCAAGCAGUACAAAUUUAAACCAGAAAUCAUGCCAGAUGACUCUGUUGAUGAAUUUGAUGAAACCAUCCACUUAGAACGAGGCGAAAAUCUAUUUGAAAUCCAUAUCAACAAAGUAACCUUUUCUUCUGAAGUUUUACAGGCAUCUGGAGAUAAAGAGCCUGUCACUUUCUGUACCUAUGCUUUCUAUGAUUUUGAACUACAGACAACUCCCGUAGUGCGAGGCCUUCAUCCCGAAUAUAACUUCACUUCUCAAUAUCUUGUUCAUGUUAAUGACUUAUUUUUGCAAUAUAUUCAGAAGAAUACUAUCACCCUUGAGGUCCACCAGGCUUAUAGCACAGAAUAUGAAACAAUUGCAGCAUGUCAAUUAAAAUUUCACGAAAUUCUUGAAAAAAGCGGCCGAAUAUUUUGUACAGCAAGUUUGAUUGGAACAAAAGGAGACAUCCCAAAUUUUGGCACAGUGGAAUACUGGUUCCGAUUAAGAGUUCCCAUGGAUCAAGCAAUUCGACUUUAUCGAGAAAGGGCAAAGGCUUUGGGGUAUAUAACAUCAAAUUUUAAGGGGCCAGAGCAUAUGCAGUCGUUAAGUCAGCAAGCACCCAAAACUGCUCAACUCAGUUCUACAGAUUCCACAGAUGGCAACUUAAAUGAACUUCACAUUACAAUAAGAUGUUGCAACCACCUGCAGUCCCGAGCAAGCCACCUGCAGCCACACCCAUAUGUUGUGUACAAGUUUUUUGAUUUUGCAGACCAUGAUACAGCUAUCAUUCCCAGUAGCAAUGAUCCACAGUUUGAUGAUCAUAUGUAUUUCCCAGUGCCAAUGAAUAUGGACUUGGAUCGAUACCUUAAGUCAGAGUCUCUGAGUUUUUAUGUUUUUGAUGAUAGUGAUACCCAGGAGAAUAUUUACAUAGGAAAAGUCAAUGUGCCUCUGAUUUCGUUGGCACAUGACAGGUGUAUCUCAGGAAUAUUUGAGUUAACAGACCAUCAAAAGCAUCCUGCUGGCACCAUCCAUGUUAUAUUGAAAUGGAAAUUUGCUUACCUUCCACCAAGUGGAUCAAUAACAACUGAAGACUUAGGAAAUUUCAUUCGCAGCGAAGAGCCAGAAGUUGUUCAAAGACUUCCUCCAGCAUCCUCUGUUAGCACACUAGUUUUAGCACCAAGACCUAAACCAAGACAACGUUUAACACCUGUAGAUAAGAAGGUAUCUUUCGUGGAUAUCAUGCCACAUCAGAGUGAUGAGACUUCUCCUCCUCCUGAAGAUAGGAAGGAAAUUUCACCAGAGGUAGAGCAUAUACCAGAAAUAGAAAUUAAUAUGCUGACUGUUCCACAUGUUCCCAAGGUUUCACAAGAAGGCAGUGUAGAUGAGGUAAAAGAGAAUACUGAGAAAAUGCAGCAAGGAAAAGAUGAUGUGUCUUUACUAUCUGAAGGUCAGCUUGCAGAACAAAGCUUGGCAUCUUCUGAAGAUGAAACAGAAAUAACAGAGGACUUGGAACCAGAAGUUGAAGAGGACAUGUCAGCUUCUGACAGUGAUGACUGUAUUAUUCCAGGUCCUAUCUCCAAGAAUAUCAAACAGGCCAUUUACAUUGUAACAUAUUCUUCAUUGGAUUUGUCUGGUGUUUCCUCAAGAUCAGAUUCCAGUUAUGCAUUUUGGUAGGAAUACAGAAGCGAUACUGUGUGCUCUUCAUUGCAUCAUAUCAGGAGGUAGAAAAUGUCAUUUUGCCUAAUUAUUGAUGGUGUUAACUUUGGUUGAAGUGUUGUUUCAUAAAUCCUUUUGUAAGCUUAAAAAUACUUGUGGUUCAUUAGUUUUUUCUUUUGUCUUCUCUAAGAACUGCUUCUGGUAAAAAUCUCAGAACAGUGAAACAUAGCUUUCAUAGGAAGGAAUGUAUUACUGAAUGCCUGUUAUGUGCUAAGUACAUCCUAUGUUAAUAUUUCCUCACAACAAUUCUUUAUUUAUUAGCAUCCAUCGUGUGUCAGGCAGGCAUAAAAGAAGCAGUUCUUUCCCUCAAAGAAUUCAUAGUCUGUAGGGGAAACACAAUUAAAAUGCAUAGUGGUCUGCACCAGGAGAAUGGAAUGCAUGGGGUGCUAUGGGAGCAUUCAGAAGGGGUCCCUAAGUCAGCAUGAGGGGUCUUCCCUUCAUCAAGGAUGACUUCCUAGAGUCAGUAAAGCUGGAGCCAGUGUUGAAGAUGAUUAGGAGUUCAUGAAAAGGGUGAGAAAAUCAUAGGCCAAAGGAAUGAAAAGCAUGAGAAUCUGAGAGAACGUAGUGCAUGGCUUGUUCUGGAAUUCAGAAUGGUUUCAGGAUGGGCCAAGCCUAUUAUGGUAUGCUUAGGGAGCCCAGGAGAAUAGGCUGAAAAGGGAGGCAUAAUCCAGAGCGUUGAGGCCUCUGAGAUUUUUAAGGAAUGGGGAUAGAAGAUCACCCAUUCAUUAAACAGAUAUAUAUGUAGUGGGCAUUUGCUGUGUUCCUAGCCUUGUUCUAGGGACUGGGAAUAGAUCCACGAAUACAAAAAAUUAAGCUCCUGAUCUUAAGGAGUUUGCAUGCUUGAUCACAUUUUGAAAGAUCAUGCUGUCAAUAAUGUAAAAAACAGAUUAGAGGCACAAACUAGUUAGAAAGGAAUUAGAUAACCCUACUCUAUAGUUAUCCCUACUUUUUAAAAAAUUGCCUCUAUUUUAUAAUGUCACAAAAUUAGGACUAGAAGUAGUGUCCUAGAUAAGUAUCAUUUAUGCCAGUUACACUGUGAAUUUGAAUUAUCUGAUAUACUGUGUAAGCAAUUUAAGAUCAGUUUCUUUUCUUCAUGUUACAGAAUCUGACAGUUCCUAGUUAUUUCUUAGAAAUGUUGAUCCUUAAAAGGAAUCUAACAGAUUUCCCAGUACUUCUACGUAUUACUUGGUUCUUUCUCUUUUCUUCAUGUCUGUGAUGUAUAAUUAAUCAUAGAUUACUUCAUUUUGUUUCAUUUCAUUUACAACAUUUAUGAGCUUCACUUUGUCAGUAUGAAAUGCUUGUCCCCUCCUUUCCUUUCCAAAGUGGCGUAAUUAGUGUUAGCAUCUUUUUUAACAGGCUACAUAAAGUUUAGUGGCUGGAUUAAAUCAAGUCAUUAACAUAAUGUGCCACCCAAUUUGCCCCUAUCUUUCUUCGUUUCCCGGACAUCAAAGUGCCACAUAGCGCAAGUGUAAUUGGGCCUUGCUGGCCUGUCAGAUUCCGUCAGCCUGACAACUGCUGCUUUUACUAAAAAGCUUCUAGGCAUGAUAAUUAAUGGCGAGUGUGGGGGGACAGAAUUCUGAGAGAUGUAAAACUUUGGACAUUUCUCUAUGAAUAUUUUAUUAAUUUGAAUAAUCAGAAGUUAACAGUAUAAAUUUGAUGUAUAAUACAUUGAUUAAAAGCCUUGUUUCAGGUCCUCAAAACAGACAUCAAAACUGAACAUUUGCAUCUGCCAUGGCAUUAAAAAAAAUUAACAAUCCAUCUUUUGCAUUAUUUCUAAUUUUAUCAUUCAAUAGUGCAGCUUUCAUUUUUCACAACAAAAUGUAUUGCCAUGAACUCACAGCUGUCUUAAAAUGUGCCCACAGGUGAGAACGGGAAAUUACAGGCUGAAAGAGCAAUGGACUCUUCUGUGCAGUGCAUAUUUACAUCAUUCUCUUUCUCUGUUCCUACUCCUAGCAGUUGUGUGAAAACUGCCAUAUUCAAUUGGACUAAAUUGCAGUUCCACCUGGAAACUAGGUUCUCUGAACAAUGAGCUGGCAUUCCCAGGUGAUUACAAUAACGAUGUUCAGCAAAGUAUGUUUAAAACUUUGAAAGGCACAAUGCAGAAAUCAAUUCACUCGCUUUAGAAUUCGCAUAUGAAAAAUUAUUAAAUCACUUAGGAAUCAAAUAUGAUAUCUUAUCAGUGGAUAAAAUAAGCCACUCUCAAUGUUUUACAUGUGGAAGCUUAAGCUAGAUAGAGAGUAGGUUUUAAAAUAUAUUUUACUUGGCCGGGUGCGGUGGCUCACACCUGUAAUCCCAGCACUUUGGGAGGCUGAGGUGGGCAGAUUACCUGAGGUCAGGAGUUCUAGACCAGCCCAACCAACAUGGUGAAACCCUGUCUCUACUAAAAAUACAAAAAUUAGCCGGGCGUGUUGGCGGGCACCUGUAAUUCCAGCUACUCGGGAGGGGAGGCAAGACAGUCCUUGAGCCUGGGAGGCAGAGGUUGCAGUGAGUCGAGAUUGCACCACUGCACUCCAGCCUGGGCAACAGAGCAAGACUCUGUCACAAAAAUAAAUAAAUAAAAAUAAAAUAUAUUUUAUGUCAAACUGGAAAUGUUGACAUACUCUCCUAGUAGAAAUUGCUUUUAAAACUAUUUUUUAUGCUUUGCAAUUUAACUAACUCUUACUAAUAUACCAUCAACAUUUUUCCAUAACAGUAUACUCUAUUUCUUUCAACAUACCUAUAAUAUUCCAUUAUAUGGCUAUACUAUAUUUAUUUAAAUAAGCCCCUUUUGAUGGACCCUUAAGUGUUUCUAUGAUUUUUUGCUAAUACAAAUAUAUCUGCUUAAGAUGAACAUUAUUAUAUAUAACAAUGUUUGAAAAUUCAUGUUUUCUCCUAUUACACUCUUUGCCAAACUAAUGAAUAAAUUUUGCCUUAGUGAUGAUUUCAUUUAAAAAGAAACAAAUGGGGCCAGAUGUGGUGGCUGACAGCUGUAAUCCUAACACUUGAGGAAGUCCAAGGCAAGAGGAUUGUUUGAGGAUAGCAGUUCAGGACCAGCCUGGGCAAUGUAACAAGACCCCCAUCUCUACAAAAACAAUUUUUUUACAUUGGCCAAGCCUGGUGACACAUGCUUGUAGUCCUAGCUACUCUGAAGGCUGAGGUUGGAGGAUCGCUUGAGCCCAGGAGUUCAGGGCUGCAGAGCUGGGAUCAUACCACUGCACUCCAGCCUGUGUGACAGAGGAGAACCUGUCGCUGCAACACACACACACACAAAAGAAAUACAAAAAGGUCUAUAUAUAUAUUUUUAUUUGCACAUACAGACAUGACAUUUAGGUUUAUGUAAGCAAAGAAAAUGUUUGGGAAAAUGUACAUCUGACAGCGUUAGCAGUGAAUAUCUCUAGGGCAGGAGUCAGCAAACAAUGGCCCCUGUGCCAAAUCCAGCCCUCUACUGUUAUUGGAACCCAGCCACCCGUUCGUUUACAUAUUAUCUAUUGCUGCUUUCACUCCACAAGGGCACAGUUGAAUACCAUAUAGCUGCAAUGCCAAAAACAUUUGUAUUCAUCCUUUUACAGAAAAAAAAAUUGCCAACUCAUGAGUUAGGUGGUAGAAUGAAACAAGGAACUUUCAUAUUUGACAUUUGGUAAUUUAUAUUGUUGGAUUAUUUUUAAUGGUGAGCAUCGAUUGACUCAAAAAAGGAAGUAGUUAGCUAAUUCUGUACUAAAAUGUUGAAUAAUAGCAAAAGAACUGUUUAACAUGAAUAUUGUGAAAGCUUUUCUAUAAAGAUGUUAGAAGUCUCCAUGGAUGGAAGAUGAAUCUUUUUUGGUUUAGAGCAAUAUUUCUCAAAGUGUGAUCCCCAGAGUUCAGCAUCAGCAUCUGCAUCACCUGAGAAUUUGUAAGAGAUGCAAAUCCUUGGCCCCACCAGAGACCUAAUGAAUUAGAAGUUCUAUGGAGUCCACCAAUCCGUGUUUUAUCAAGUGAUUCUGGGGUAUGCUAAAAUGCAAGAACCAUAGCUUUAGAAAAAAGUGGUACUUUUCACCCUUGGCUGCACAUGAGAAUCGUCUGGGGAGCAUUGUUAAAUGCCAGGGCCCAGGCUCCACCUAGAUAAAUUAAGUCAGAAUUUUGUUUAUAGCUCCCCUGGUGAUUCUAAUGUGCAGCCAAAAUCAAGAACCACUGCACUGCAACAUCUGUUCUCAGUGAUGGUGAAAGGAGAGUAGCAUAUCAAAAUCACCUGAAAUUGAGGGUGAUUUUUAAAAUUCUCCUUGCUUCACAUUGCUGCAAUGUGUCAUAUCCCUCAGGUUUGUAUCUAUUUAUACACAUUUAUACACACACACACACCAUUUCUAUGGUGAUGAAAUAAUACCAAUUUAUAAUUAUUUGGCAUAAUUAUUUGGAGAUUAAUUUGAUAUUAGGGCAGGAAAAAAAUAAUCCAAAUCACUGCAAGGACAUAGUAAUUUAUAGGGCAUAUAAGGACACCGUGACAAUGUUCUAAAAAUAAGUACUGUUAAAGCUAGCACUGUUUUGAUCCCCAUCACUGAAGUUUGCAACGUUUACCUUAUUUGUUUAAUAUAGUACAUUUUAACAGAACAUGUUAGAAAAGAUAGAUUACUGCCACGGACGAAAACUGGGUGGUUUUCUUUUGUUUGUUAAAAACCUUAUUACCUUGACAGCUUGAGAUUCUGGAGACAUCACCUUUGUAUGUACUUAUUAUUAUUAUUUUAAAUAAUCAACAGUUGUUAAAAUAAACAGUUAAACAGUUAUUAAACAAUCAAAAUGCUUUAAUCAGAACUUGUAUGAGGAGUGGAUUUGAUGCACAAUGUAAGAGGAAGCUUUGGAGCCUGAUGUGAAGGACUGAAGGGGAUUUUUUUGAGUCUUUGAGAGGAUGUCUCUGCCCAUGCCCAGCCUGAAGAAGGGAACUUGUAAGAAUCACCAUUAAUUAAUAUGCAUUCCUACCCUACUUACAUAUGGCUCUGUCAAUACCAGUGGUUGAGUCUGAUUGUUUUAACCAACUGUUUUGAGCUUGUCUUAGAGCUCACCCCAAUUAAAAUUUGUACUCUUCAAAAGCA